AUCUGUUUAUUGUGUCUCUGUGUGGGAGAGAACUGGCUGAAGAGGUGGGGCUCCAGUUUUGGGAACAUGGACACUGAGAGAGUUGGGGAUGGAAAACAACAUAGAAGGAAGCAAAGCCAGAGGCUGCGAUGGCCAUGCUGCCUGGCCCUGGUCCCAGACAGACACCCCAGCCAGCUUUCCUCUUGCACCCUUUGUCUGCUGGCCGCAGCGUCGCAGUGGGAGUCCUGGGCCCACUUCUCCAAAUGGCACACAGAAGCCUCAACAGGCACCCACCUGGGAAAGGCCAAGGCCGAGGGCUUGGGGUGCACAGUCAAGAACACGCCUCAGCUCAGCAUUUGUGAGCCGAGUCACUUUGGCCCAUCGUUUGUACACAGCCCCCACCUGCUGGUUGACCAUGACCACAGGGCAGGCGCUGCCACAGGGCGUGGGCAGGCUGGACCUUCGAGGGCCUCCUCUGUCUCCCCUACCUUCUGCCCCCCCACCACUUCCCAUCACCCAGUCUGUGCCAAGGGCACUGACCCUGUCCUUGUCUUGCAGGAAGAGGAGCAGGACUUGGAUGGUGAGAAGGGGCCAUCAUCGGAAGGGCCUGAGGAGGAGGACGGAGAAGGCUUCUCCUUCAAAUACAGCCCCGGGAAGCUGAGGGGAAACCAGUACAAGAAGAUGAUGACCAAAGAGGAGCUGGAGGAGGAGCAGAGAGUUCAGAAGGAACAGCUGGCUGCCAUCUUCAAGCUCAUGAAAGACAACAAGGAGACGUUUGGCGAGAUGUCCGACGGCGACGUGCAGGAGCAGCUCCGGCUCUACGACAUGUAGACUGCGCCCACGGGAUGCACAGCGGCCAUGCCUGAUGCUGUCCCCACCCUUGCCCCAUGCCCUUGUUCUUUCCAGACUUCUGUAGGCCUAAUUUUCCCUUAUAAACAUAGAUGCAGGCGUACAUUCUAUAGGUACUUGCCGAGUUCUUGCAGUGUGUAUAUUACUUUGCAGGAAUCAAAAUUGUUUUAUUCAGAAGACAAAGUCCCUGACCCCUCUGGUUUCUGCUUGCUGGUGAGGUUCCAGCUGUUAUUGGGCUCUGAGGCCCUCUCCUGAUCCAAAUCUUUUUUUGUUUGUUUGAGAUGGAGUCUCACUCUGUCUCCCAGGCUGGAGUGCAGUGGCGUGAUCUUGGCUCACUGCAACCUCCACCUCCCUGAUUCAAGCGACUCUCCUGCCUCAGCCUCCCGAGUAGCUGGGAUUGCAGGCAUGCACCAUCACACCUGGCUAAUUUUGUAUUUUCAGUAGAGACAGCGUUUUGCCAUGCUGGCCAGGCUCGUCUCGAACUCCUGACCUCAGGUGAUCCGCCCACCUUGGCCUCCCAAAGUGCUGGGAUUACACGCGUGAGCCACCAUGCCCGGCCAAUACUACACUCUUAUUCUGCCUUACGAGGAUUUCUGGAAGCUUCUGUAACUGUAGGGAAGAAAGCUGUAGGGGAGCAUGGUUUUUUUGUUUUGUUUUUGUUUUUGAGACGAGGUCUCACUGUCACCCAGGCUGGAGUGCAGUGGUGCCAUCAUGACUCACUGCAGCCUUGACCUCCCAGGCGCACAAAAUCCUCCUCUCAGCCUGAGUAACUGGGACUACAGGUGUGUACCACUACAUCCAGCUAAAGGAGAGCGUUUUUUUCUUUUUCUUUUUGAGACAGAGUCUCACUCUGGCGCCUGGUCACUGUGCCCUUCACCUUCUGGGUUCAAGUGAUUCUCCUGCCUCAGCCUCCCUAGUAGCUGGGAUUACAGGCAUGCACCACCAUACCCAGCUAAUUUCUGUAUUUUUAGUAGAGAUGGAGUUUCACCAUGUUGGCCAGGCUGGUCUCGAACUCCUGACCUCAGGUGAUCCACCUGCCUCGGCCUCCCAAAGUGCUAGGAUUACAGGCGUGAGCCACCAUGCCCAGCUGGGAGCGUUCUUUCAGCAAAAAGUCUAAUUCAGAGACUCACCUUCCAUCCUGGCACUAAACAAUAGUACUAGAGGUAAGAUCUGCCAAGAAUUUCUCUCACUUAAGCAGGAUACUUACUUUAAAUAUAAUUAGGCAAGACUUAUUUGAGUACUUGCCUAAUUGUAUUUAAUUAGAACUAUGCUGGAUGCUGUAGACAGAAGAAAUAAAAUACUCAACUUGGUCCCUAUCUUCCAGCAGGUUAGAGGCCUUUAGGGAAGAAAAGCCUGUGUGCAGGGAAAGAGAACCUCACCAGAAAGUAUUCAAUAAAAUGCCAAAGUGAUCUUACAGAACAGUGCCUGUGACACCGGAGGGGAUUGUUCUGUCUUUGUGAGUGAACAUACAAUGAUGGGGAUAACUGGUCCUCAUACCAUGCAGGUCCCAUUUCUGAUCACCCCACUGGCAGGACAAUUCACAGUUCUUGAGCAAACUGAGUUAGGGAGGGUAUGCUAACGACAGAACCUAUGCAAGUUCUUAGAAAUAUUUUUUGUUUGCUGAAAUAAAGCUCAAUCAACACACUACCUUAAAAAAAAAGUGGAGCAGUGGCAUUUCCAUGCCUCAUGCUCACCAUCAUGAGGUUAACUUCCCGCCGUCGCCUCUUGCCUGCCAGGGGUUUUUCGGGAGCCCCUCUCUGUUCCACUCUGAUUCCUUUUGUUUCUUGCUGACCAUUCACUCUCUGUGUCUGUUGUUGGAUCCAAAUACGAGUGUUUUUCUUUCUUUUUGUGGUCAGUGCUUUUUUCCUUCUUGAAAUUGUUUUAAUGUGUUUUGUCAAAAGCAUUUAACCAUGUUAUGAUUUAAGAAUUCUCUGUUCACUUGAGGUCAGGAGUUCAAGACCAGCCUGGCCAAUAUGGCAAAACCCUGUCUCUACUACAAAUACAAAAAUUAGCCAGGCGUGGUAGCGCACGCCUGUAAUCCCAGCUACUCAGGAGACUGAGGCAGGAGAAUCGCUUGAACUCAGAAGGCGGAGGUUCCAGUGAGCCAUCGCGCCACUGCACUCUAGCCUGGGUGACAGAGCAAGACUCUGUCUCAAAAAAAAAAAAAAAAAAAAAAAAAAAUUAUUUGUUCUGUCUCAGGUCUUAGGGACCCCUUACCUCAGCUAAUGUCUCUGUCCCCUAAAUGCACAUCGGUGGGCAGGGCAAACCCGUAGGUGCCCUUAUCCCUCCCAAGGCUGCACUGCAAAGCUCCUGUGUUUCCAUUGCCCACUUUCUUCUCCCUCUCCUUUCUUUUCUGAUUAUACCAAACAGGAAUGACUCGUGUACUUGAGUCAAAAUCCUGAUGGCAUUGGGAAAAGUAAACUGAAGGAAUUUUUGUACACUUGUACCAGCUAAGAUGUUCUGACUGCAACGACAGAAAACUCCAGCUCAACUGGCUUAAACAAGAACAGGGCUCUCUCACGUGAGAAGCCAAGAGUUAGAACAACUCCAGGCCCAGAAUGGUCGGAGCUCAAGCUGCAGUUCUCUUAGCUCAGUCUUCCUCGUACUGUGGGCUUUUAUUGGAGACUAGCUCUCCUCAUGGUGGCAAGAUGGCUGCAGGAGUUCAGGUAUCUCAUCCAGAAGCAAGAAAAGGGCAUGUCUUGCUUGCGUCUCUAGGCGUAAGGGAACUGGUCCAGAUGUCCCCGCCCCACAUCCCUUCAGAUCCCAAUUGGCCAGAAUAUGGCACGUGCCCAUGUUUCAACCAAUCAUGGGCAAGGACAUGGGACCAGCAUGAUUGGCCUAGACCCCUGGAGCCUGGGGCUGGGCCCAGCAUCCCCUGAAUACAUGGCCAUCUGGAGGAGAAGGUAACUGAAUUUCACUGGGGAUCUGUGAUAAAAGGGAGCAUGGGUGUUGGGGAGACACCUGUUCCAGUUGGGUUUCCUAUGAGGUCCAGGACAGGGCUUGGUGGGCACUCGGAAGCCAGUGUCUGAAGUGCUCAGCAUCCUCCUCUUCCUCGGUGGUGGGUGUCCACCGCCCAGGCCCCACCCCUGGCCUUGGACACUUCAUGGAAACACUGCUGAUUUGCUGUGGUGUUGGGUGGCUCCUAUCUAUUCCCCGUAAGUGCUGGCCUCUGUUGACACCAUUUCUGCUACCUCAUCUGAGAUUGUUCUCAUCAGCUCACAGAGAUUCAUUUCAGUGAAUGAACCAAAUCUAAGCUAAAAAGCAUAAAGGAGGGCAGAAAGAAACAGCAGUGUGGGAGAAAGAGCGCAAACACCGAGAGAAAGAUGUCUACCUGGCAGCCAUGUCAGAGAAUCACCAGUAUGUAUGUCACUGCCACCAAGAACCUAAGAGCCACAGAGGCCUACAGAAGCCAAUCCCAAUGGAACUCUCUCUGGGUGUGGGGGUUGAGAGAACCUAAAGCAUUCAGCUGCACAGAGCCUCUUUCCAGCGAUGGGAACCAGUCUCAAAGCCUUUACAUCUCUCCCCUGCCCUCCAUCACUGCUGAGAACCCUGCCCCAGGCUGGCCUGCCUACAUGACACAAAUAGCAGUGGACUGUCACUCAUCAGUAUCUGCAGUUCUGUUUACCAAAGCCUGCUUGCUAGAGACGUUUCAGGGCCUCCUUCCCUCAAAGCGUCCACUGUACCUCCAUCUGGAUACAAUUAGCUGGCUCCCCACUUCCUGGACUGACGGUAACCACCUUUUCCAAUGACCCUGAAGAAAACAUGCAAUCUAAGCUGCUUUAAGAGUAACCUACAACUGAGGACAAAUUUUCUAUCAACUCCCAGUACCCCUCUCUGCCGUGGCUGAUUUGUUACUGGUUUUCCUUUUUUUUUUUUAAUUUGAAAAUGUAAGUAAUUAUACUAAGACCAGAUCACUCUGAGAUUGUUUUAUUCUAAUUUGUCCUAAGGACCUGCCUGUACUUAGAGCCUGAUAGAAAGCCCAAGUUGAUCUACUGGGCAGCUCUCUGGGCCUGGAAGGAAGAGCACACAACAAGACUUCAACAGUGAGCCUGGCUAGGUCCAGGCAGACCAUGAUUUCUGAAAGCAACAGUAUAGUCCACAUGGAAUCAGGCUGCUGAUGAACAGCAGCGAGAGGCUGCCUCUGAAUCAUAUCUGCAGGGUCACCUGCGCCUGGUGGAGGCCCACAGUCAUCCAUUAGGCCCCAGUAUCCUAUGUGGGAGUAUCCACGUCUAGUCUCUACUUCUCACUGCAGGAGAGGUGGCAGAUGAGGAGGUUUCCUACUUUAAAGAAAGUAGAAGUUGUUUCCUUUCUUCCCUCCUCACAGCCUUGAGGGGGAGGUUGUGCCCAGCCUGACAGCAGCUGCCUUGCCCAAGAUUACAUCCUGUUCUGGGGGCAGCCCACCUCCAAACCAAGUCACUAGUGGGGUACAAAGGCCUGCCCUCUCUGCCAAAAGGCAGGUGCUGAUGGACCAUUCCAGUUCUAGAGUUCCCAAAGAGACGUCUUUUUGGAGAGCGGCAGGGUACCAGAAAUCCUUCACUCAGGCUAUAGCAUGGCCACCAAUUAUAAGUAACUUGAGGCCCACCCAGCCAAACAUGCCUUUCCGGGUCUAGUGCUGGGUUCCAGAACAGGAAGCCUGGCAGAUUCCUACUGCCACAGAUUCUUUUUACUAUUAUUAUUGUCACCUUAUUUUUCUUUUGGUGGAACCCCUCUAGGGCUUCCACCGGAUUCUCCACCAUUUACGCUAUCAAUUUUAUCAGUUUUGGUUUUAUCGUUUCAGUGCUUCUUUUUGCUAACGGUAGCAGCCAAUAUACAUCAUCUCUGGAGACAAAUCACGCCAUAGAAAAUAUUGUAGUUUUCCUCAUUUUUCUUAACGCCACAGAGUCAGCUGGGCUGUAGUACCAGCCCGGAUGUACCAGUUUACUCAGCCACUCCCCCUCUCAUGGACAUCUGCAUGGUUUCCAGUCUUGCAAAUUCAUACAGUGCCACUACAAAUAAAACCUUGCGCGUAUGCUGUUUUCA